AUGGCAGAAAACAAAGGGUUAGGGUACCCGGAUGCCAGGUUCUCAGUGCUGGUGUCCUCACAACUGGCUAUCCCUAUGCCCCUGCUGUCCUCAGGUUCCCCUGUCCUCCUCUGCGACCCUGGCCCCUGGCCCACUCAUUUGCGCGCAGCUGUGCUCUACAUUCCCACCCCCUGCUCCCUGCAAAACCCCACUGCCCUGCAGGCUACAAAUCCAAAGAUUGGGUGCUCAUCAGAGUUGGAGAAGCCAUAUUGGAGGGGAGGGGUCCCAAAGGCUUCCUCCUUGCCAUCCUUUCUCGGGGACUGUGGCUUGGUCAUGAUGUGUGGCCUGGGUUUGGAUUUGUAUUGUGAGGAAGAGGAGACAGAGUGGGCCCCGCAGCAAGGCAUCUGGAAAGCUCCUUUCCUGCUCCUGACAGUCACCCCGAACGGCAUGUUUCCAAAUCCACAGAACAUAUGGGCUGCAGAGCUCAGAGCCUUGCUCCUGGCCCAGCCAACAGGAUGCUCUCUUCUUUCCCUGGCGUGGACCACACCCCAUCUAGACCACACCCCAUCUAGUCCACACCCCAUCCAGGCCACACUCCAUCCAGUCCACACCCCAUCUAGACCACACCCCAUCCAGUCCACACUGCACACAGUCCAUGCCCCAUCCAGACCACACCCCAUCCAGUCCACACUGCAUCCAGUCCAUUCCCUGUCCAGACCACACCCCAUCCAGUCCACACCCCAUCCAGACCACACACCAUCUAGUCCAUGCCCCAUCCAGACCACACACCAUCUAGUCCAUGCCCCAUCCAGACCACACACCAUCCAGACCACUACUCCAUCCAGUCCUCACUGCAUCCAGACCUCAGUCCAUCUAUCUAGUCCACACCUCACCCAGACCAAUCUCCAUCCAGUCCACACUCCAUCCAGUCCACACCCCAUCAAGAUCACUACUCCAUCCAGUCCACACUCCAUCCUGUCUACACCCCAUCCAGUCCACACCCCGUCCAGUCCACACCCUGUCCAGUACACACCCCAUCCAGUCCACACCCCAUCCAGACCACACCCCAUCCAGUACACACCCCAUCCAGUACACACCCCUUCUAGUCUACACUCCAUCCAGACCACACCCCAUUCAGUCCACGUUGCAUCCAGUCCACACCCCAUCCAGACCACACCUCACCCAGACCACACCCCAUCCAGUCCACACCCCAUCCAGUCCACACCCCAUCCAGACCACACUGUAUCCAGUCCACGCCCCAUACAGACCAUACCCCAUCCAGACCACACCUCACCCAGACCAUCCACGCCCCAUCCAGACCAUACCCCAUCCAGACCACACCUCACCCAGACCACACCCCAUCCAGUCACACUGCAUCCAGUCCACACCCCAUCCAGACCACUACUCCAUCCAGACCACACCCCAUGUAGUUCACACUCCCCCAAGUCAACACCCCAUCCAGUCCAUGUUCCAUCCAGUUCAUGCCCCACACAGACCACGCUCCAUCCAAUCCACGCCCCACCUCGACCACUACUCCAUCCAGUUCAUACUGCAUCCAGUCCAUACUCCAUCCAGUCCACUGUCCACCCCGACCAUGUUCAUCUGACCCAUGCUCCAUCCAGUCCAUGCUCCAUCUGGUCCUCUGCUUUUACCCUACAGUGUCCACUCUUGUCCUCUCUCUUCUUGGCUUAGUCCCCUCAUCCUUUAUCUUCUAAUCUAAACUUCUGAGAAGUUUUCCUGAUUGGCGAGAGCCUCUUGUUAAAUGCUCUCUGCUCCUUCACAACACUUUGGCCUCCUCACAUUUUGAAACCAAUUCUCUGCAAUAACUACUUUAAUGUUGGUUUUCCCCACAACGCUAGCAGCUGCAGGAAGGCAGAGACUGUGUCUUAUUUACUGGUCUAGCUCCAGCACCUCACAGAUGUUCAGUAAACACAAGUUUAUUUCUACGAGUGACCACAUGGAAAAUGUGAGUGGGCUGGAGGAGAGGUGCAGGCAGGGUGCUGUGGAGGGUCAGGGAUGCAAAGGCCUGAGUUGGCUGAGGUGGGGUCGGGCUCGUGGAAGAACUGCCAUUUGGUUGGGCUUCAGAGAGAUGUAAGCAGACACGGGGUCUGGGUGGAGGAGUAGUGCCAGCAAAGGCAUGUGGACAAUGCACGGGGUAUGGAGGGUAAUCUCUUAGACUAGACUAGCUCACACUUGGAGGGAGCAGGGGAGCAUGAUGCCUUGAAUGACUUCCUAAGGAGUUAGGACUUCAACAACUGAGUUGCAGGGCCCCGUCUACACUGGGGUUCAGGACUUUAGAGGACAACCGAGCUGUCCUGCAGGGCUGCUGAGGGUUCUGCCCUUGUCCUUUCCCUGGAGGCUAACAAAUCAUUGCUUUGCAUUCCAUUCACAUGGGAUAGUUGUGCCAUGAAAGGGGAUGGAGAAAAUCAAGGAAGACCUCCUGAAGGAGGUGGAGAGGUUAAUCAGGAGCUGGAGGAACGCACUGCCCACUCAGCUCUGUGGUUUGAGUCUCCAAAGGUGGUCUAGAGCAUGGCGAGGACCAUCGGAACUUGGGUGAGCUAGGGAAGUUUUUACCUAGAGGUUGAGGGUCCCCUUUUAUAUGAUGAACUGUGCUCUUGGAGUGUCCCAUUUGCCAUGCAGAACAAAACACUGCCCUUUAUCUUGAUGAAGAGAUAGUUGACCACAUAAUGGCCAAAGCAUGGUCAGUAUUGUACAUUUUGCCUUGUCGCAGUCUUUCCAAGUUGACAUGGCCUUCCUGGAGGAAUUACCACUUAGGGUAGAGGCACCCCUUCCCCCAUCAAUGCCACUGCCCCACAUUGGAGGAGGGGUUGUUUAUGUUCACCAUGUGCCUGCUUCCAAUGCCAAAUCCAGCCUCAGAAAGCUUUCUGGAAGUGACGCCAACUUCAGGGGCAAGGCCCUGGUUCUGGGGUCAGCACCAUUCCGUGGUUCCUGAAGAGAUGGUAGACUAUGGAACGUAGGCGUUAUGAUUUCUGACCUAUGUAACAUGGUCCACUAACUCUCAGUAUCCAAUCCAUCCUCGGAGGGCUUCCUGGAGGUGUUGCCAACUUCAGGGAAGAGAACACGUGGUUUAGCUUCAGCACUGCUCCACGGCAAUUUCUGUGGCUCAUGGUUGAUGUCUGACUUGUGCAACAAGGCCUGGCUCUUCUGGGCACUAAAUGCACUCUCUGGGGAGUUUUCUGGAAGUGAUGCAACUUGGGCUCAAGACACCGGUUCCAGCCUCAGCCGUGGUUCUGGAAGAGAUGAUUUGCCAUGUGGCCUGUGCGAAAGGAGGGAUUUGUGUGAGAUGGGCUACCACUUCCCAGUAGCCUGCCAGCUUUGGAGGGCUUCGUGGAGCCAAUACUACCUUCAGGGGGACCCACCAGUCCAUCCUUCAUUCCGCUGUGUGGCAUUGAAGAGUUGCUUUCCUGUGUUGAAGUUUUCUGUUUAUACCAAUGUCCACCUCUGAUCAAUCUUACAUUCAGUCUCAGGGUUUUCCGGAGGCAGUGCCAAGUCUGGGAAUGAGACAGUGGUUCUGUCCUUAGGGAGGUGGUUGACCAAAACAACUCCUGCUUUGUUCAUGAAGAUGGCAUGGUGGUUACUGCUCAGAAUCUAAUCCAACCUAAGAGGACCUCCUGGAAAUGCCCUUGGUAUUGAGGCAGAUAUGGCCUUAGGGCACUUUUUUUUUUUUUUUAAUGCCCAAGACUAGAGCUCACUAAUAGGUAAGAUCUGGGCCUCAGGUGCCCAGUACUGUUUCCUUGGCCUGGUUAGUGUAACUAGAUGGAUGUUCUUUGGUUGCACGUGGGCCAUUUUGUAUUUCUGAUUUUCUCCCCACUCCCCUAACCAGCUCUGUUAGCCAUGUGCCAUGUCCUCCCUCCCAUCUACCCACUCCUUCAGACCCAGCACAGUGCGCCUGGCACACAGCAGGCACUUAAUCAGUAUUUAUGGAGUGAUGAAAUCCAUAUCAUCGUCCACUUCUUCUCAGUGGGACUUUCGGCCUCGAAGGGCUUCCUGGAGGAGUUGCCAGUUUUGGGGAUGAGCCACUGCUUCGAGCAUUCAUGUCAACCCCCGACCAUGAAGACGAGACUCCUGGCCUGUGUGUGCUUGUCGCAUGAUGCAUGUGCUGUGCUCAACCUCCCUUCUGGUUCCACCCAGCUCAAGGCCUUGGAGGGCUUUCUGGAUGUGUCCUGAGCCUUUGUCCUCGGCAUCUCUGUGUGGUACUUGGAGAGAUAGUAGACCGUAUAGCGUACGCUUUAUCUGUGACGUAUGUAACACGGUCCACUAACCCUCAGUAUCAAAUCCAUCCCCGAGGCUCCUGGAAACAACGCUGUCUUCGGGGAGGAACGGUUGGACCCACCACCACUUCUCCAUGACACCCGAAGAGAUGAUUUUCUGUAUGGCAUGUGUUUUUCUGCAUGAUGCAAAAUGGCAUAAUCUCGCUCCUCUUAAAUCAAGUUCUGCCUUGGGAAAUCGCGCCAUCCCUGGGGAGGAGACCUUGAUUCUUCCCGGAAUCAGUGCCAUUCCAUGGUGCUCAAUGACGUGGUUGACUACGCUACGCUUAUUCAGUAGACACCGUGACCUGCUUCUUCUCAGCGUCAAAUGCAGCCUAGAAGAAGCGCCCUCAGGCAACUUCGUGGACAUGAGCCUUCUUCCAGCCACCACCACCACCAUCGUGCGGUACUUGAAGAAAUGGUUUACCGUCCCACAUACAUUUUGAAUAUGUAUGUGGGAUGGUAAACCGCUUCUUGGUAUCCAGCCCAGCCAUCCAAACCUCCCUGGAGAAAGCCUGGAGUUAGAGGAGAGCCACGGGUCUCGGCAUCCGCCAUGCCAUGGCACUUGGUGGAAUGGUAGACUCUUAGAUGUGUGCUUUCUCUGUCAAUGCUUGUGAUGCGGUCUUCUCCUCAGUGCCAAACACAGCCUCCAGUGACUUCCUCAGGACAAGGAUGACCUCCAGGAAGGUGUCCUACUGCCCACGUUGGCACAUCCCUCUGGAGUAAUUGAAGAAACGGUGGCUGGUGCCGCAAAUGUUCAUGAACGAGGGAUGUGAAACAGGUCACCUCUCAUCCUCAGAGCCCUCCUCAGAUGACUUCAGGACAGUACGCCCAUGUAGGAGCAGAUAUGGGUCCAGGAGAUGAUGCCACUCCAGGUACUUGAAGACGCACUGACUCGUUUUUGUCUUUGCUGAUGCGUGUACAGUCUAUCUUUUUUCCAUCUCAAGUCUAGCCAUCUCGGGGGAAGAUGUCCCAGCUCUGGACUCAGCACUGAUCCUCAUGAAGAGCUGCUCGACCCCAUCGUGUAUGUUUACAGAGGAAGUGCCUCCAUGGCCCACUUCUUCCCUAUCUCCAUCCCAGAACCCUUGCUUGGAGAACUUGCUGAAGAAGCUGCCAGCCUCAGGGACAGAGCACUGGUUCUGGCCUCUUCACUGACCUCACGGUACCUGAAAAGGGUUCAGCCACACUGCAUGUCUUUUCCCCAUGACGUAUGUAACAUGGUCUACUUCUUUUGAAGUAUCCCAUUCAGCCUGGAAAGUCUCCAGGGAGGUUAUGUUAAGCUUAGGAGACAAAGCACCAGUUCUGGUACAAGUACUGCCUCGGGGUACUUAGUAGAAGUUGGCCAUGCUUCAUAUGUUUUACUUACAACGCAUGUUACUUCGUCCACCUUCCUAUAACAGCGUGCACCUCGGGGGGCUUUCUGUAGGCAGGAACGAGUGUCAGUCAUAGCACUAGUUCCAGCAUCAUCUCCAUUCUUGAGGGGCUCCUUUGUGCUGCGUCCACUGCAUCUGCGGCAGACAUUGCAUGGUGGCCUCUUCUCAAUACUACAUCAGGCCUCAGAGGGCUUCCUGGAGGUGAUGCUAGUGAGAGGAAAGAGACACCGGCUCUGACCUCAGCCCUCUCCAAGGUACCUGAAAAGAUGGUUGACCAUAGAACAUGCGCUAUCUCUGUGUCGUAUGUAAUAUGGUCCACAUCUUCUCAAUAUCAAAUUCAGUCAUAGAGGGCUUCCCAGAGAGAGGCAAAGUCACCUUCGUGGGAGACACACUGAUCUGGCUUCAGCGCCAUUCCACAGUACUUGGAGAGAUGGUAGAGCAUAAAGCAUAUGCAUUGUUGAAUGACAGAUGUAGCAUGGUCCACUCAUUCUCAGUAUCAGCCAGCCCUGGGGCUUCCCGGAGGCCAUGCCGACUUGAGAGCCAGGCCUGAGUGGUAGCCAGGGUGCAGUGCAGGUCACCGGGUGGUUGGCUGCAGACCCAGUCCUUUAUUUAUUACAUUGGCCAUUUGGUCCACCAGCCAAGAACUCAGUACCGGUCCCACCCUUACAGGGCAUCCUGGAGGUGGUAGUGGCAUUGGAUGUGGGUUUGUGGUCAUUGCCACAUUGCCGGUGGCUGGUAGUUCAUGAUGCGCAUUGUGAGGCUUUCUGGAGGUGAUAGCAGGUGAAAGGAAGAGAGCCAGGGGUCAGCGUCACUUCCUGGUAUUUGAAGAUGCGGUUGACCAUGGUGUGUACGCUUUAUUUGUGACGUAGGACACAUGGUCUACUUCUUCUCAAUAUCACAUCUCGCCUUGGAAGACUUCCAGGAGGUGAUAUCAGCUUUGCGGAAGAGCCACUGUCCUGGUGUCAGUACGGCUGCUGCUUGGUACUUGGAGAGAGGUGGUCCGUGGCGCGUUCGCUUUAUUUAUGGCGCACAUUACACGGUCGACCUCUUUGCAGUAUCUAAUCCCGCCUUGCAAGCUUUCCUGGAGCUAACAUCAACUGCGGGGGUGGGGGCCACUAGGUCUGCGCUCAGUGUGACCCAGCGGGGUUUGUGAUGUGUUUGUCUUGUGUGUGACGAUAACUCACGUGUGGCAGCCUUCUUCUCAGCACACUGCUCUGGCUUGGCAGCAGGGUUAACUUGCGGACAAGGAGCGUGGUGUCAGCACGUGCCUGGAUACAUGAGAUGGUUGACCAGAGAGCACACGCUUUAUUUGUGCCGUUUGUGACCUGGUCCACUAACCCUCAGUAUCUAAUGCCCCCUUGGAGAACUUCCUGGAAGAGGUGUCAACUUUUUGGGAAAGAGACAGUAAACUGGGGCCAGCUGCACUCUGUUAGACUCUGAAGAGAGCAUCUGCGAGGCGUUUGCGACAUGUAUGCCAAAUGUGGCUGAGUUGGACUGAUUUUCACUCCGAUCUCUUUCCUUGGAGGGCUUCCUAGAUGUGGAGGCAUCCAAGUUCAAGGGAAGGGGCAUGCUGUCUAUACCAUCCCAAAGUCCUCCAGUGAUCAGCUGACCUGAGUGUAUGCACUUUAAUUUACAACCAAGGUCGCCUGGCCCGUCACACCUCAGUCUCCACUGGGUCCUUAGCAGGACCUUUGGUGGAGUCAGCCUUGCUUUGGGGCAUCUGUGCCUCUCUUGAGUAACUGAGAAAAGAUGGCCCUGGAGGUUAACCCUAAACGCGAUAGCUGCUGUGACCAGCCUUUUUAUGGCAUCACCACCUCUGGCUGUGAUGUCAACUUCCAGACGUGAUGUGGGGUCUGCUCCACUGGGGUACUUGGAUAGAUGGUUGGCAAGCAGCAUGCAUCCAACUCUUGGCUUCUUCCGGCAAAUCAACUAACUAACGCUCAGUGUGCAAUUCCAUAUUUAACAGGACUUCCAGCACUGAAUGUCAAGUCUGGGGAAGAAUCAGUGGUGUUCUUGUCAGUGUUAAUCAGUGGUACCUGAAGAGAGGUUUUCUGGGUUUCUGUUUCUUUAAUGAGGACGAAACACACCUGGUUAACCUCUUUUCCAGUAUCAAAUCCCAUCUUGGAGGCCUUCUGGUCCAGACCUCAGCUUCAGGGAAGGGCGUUACUCUCAGCUCCAGUCCACUGGACAGAAAUCUAUGGUUAACCACGAAGCCUGUGCUGUAUUAUUUUGACUGAUGUCAUCUGUUCUACUAACCCCAGUGUCCAAUCCGUAUUUAACAGGACUUCCAGGACUGAAUGUCAAGUUUGGGGAAGGAAUCAGUGGUGUUCUUGUCAGUGUUACUUGGUGGUACCUGAAGAGAGGUUUUCUGGGUUUCUGUUUCUUUAUUGAGGACGAAACACACCUGGUUAACCUCUUUUCCAGUAUCAAAUCCCAUCUUGGAGGCCUUCUGGUCCAGACCUCAGCUUCAGGGAAGGGGUGCUGUGGACAUAAAUAAGGAGACACGAGCAAAUGGCUGAUCACUAAGCGUGCCCCAUGUUUCUGAAUUUUGCCACCGAUUGCGCUAACCCUCAAUGUCUUAUCCCUUCUUAGGAGGACUUUUCAAUGUGAUGGCAGCCUGGGGGAAGACAGUGUCACCACGACAGUGUCACGGAACAUGCAGGUGAGUUGUCUGUGGUUGCCUUCGUUGUGCUCCCAACGGAUCGUGUGUGUAAUUCAGGCUCUUUCGGCAUCUGACCCUGCUGUAGGGGGAUGCCUCGUCCUUGCCACACUCAGUGAUGGGCUUGAAUGAGCCCAGCCCACAGCAGGGGAAUGCCAGCAUGCCCUGGACAGAUAGUGCAGGUGUCCUGCACGCCUGCCCCUAGCCUGCAGUUUAUUCUGAAAGGAUGUCCUGGAUAUAAUGACACCUUAGGGAAGAAAAGCUGAUUCUGAGGUCAAGAGGAGACCUUGGGGGCCCUGGAAUUGGCCCAGGUUGAGACCUGUUUAUUUCUCACAGGAAUUGUGGAGUUGACUUCCUUUAAAUCUGGAGGAAUCCUUGAUGUCAUGCCAGCUUGAAGGGAGGGCAUUGUCACCAGCCCUGAUCCAGGGGAAGGGAGUGGAUGGCCCACCACGGGGCAUGUACCUCCCCAGGAACACACCUGCUCCACUGACCAGCACAUCUGACCUACCCUCAGGGUUGUGUUUCUGCAGAUGGUCCUUCUUUGGGGUGCUCAAGGAGAGGUUUCCUUUGGCAUAUCUGUUUCUUUUAUAUAAAUCAUUUCUGUGGACCACUCUUCAGUAUCAAACACCAGUUUGGAAGGCUUCCGGAUAAGACAGUUGUCAGGCCCAGGCCAGGGUGAGUGGGCCGAGAUGGGUGCUUCCCCUGUUCUAAGCGUCCUGUCUGGCAGUAAUGCUUGGUGCCCGAUCCUUUCCAGGAGGACUUCCUGGAGGUGAUGCCAGCCUCUGGGGAAGGAAAAGGCUCCCUGCCAGCUCUAAAGCCAAGGCACAGAAGUAGGUUUUGCUGGUGCUGCAUUUGUUUUGAUGGCACUUAGCUGUGACUGUGGGUCCUCGGCUCAUCUGUGGCAUUUGGGGAUGGGACUGUGAGGGAGGAGGGCCUCAGGUUCUGGAGAAGGGCCAGGUAUUUCCAUGUCAACCCUGCUUUUUAUAACCAGAGAGAACAUAUGAGGUAGCACCAAUGACCUCCGCCACCAAUCCUUCCUAUUAGCUGAUACCCAAACACCGUUCCUUCCAGCCGAAAAGAGCCCUCAUAAAGAGAGGGCAGAGAGAGUGUGUCAAGGCCAUGUGACAGCAGGCAGUAUGCUGUUGCCUCCGGGGUAUCCAGGGUAGGCGGCUGCUGGGUCCAUGUAGAUUGGGUGCUCUGCUGGCUACGGAGGGGUCAAAGGACAGGUGGCAAGGGUGCAGAGCCGCAGCCUGGCCCUGGGAUUUUCUUCUCAGACCUCUGCUCCGGGGUCCACCUUCGGGGGAAAAGAGGGCACAAUUUUACAACUUUGUAAGAGGAAACCUGAAGUUUUCUGACCCCUGAUUCUCCCCAGCCCUGUCAGGAUUGAUCUAACUCUCUGUUGAGAUGCAAAAGAGUCUGGAGAUAACAGUACUCCCCCCACCAUGAAAACAAUUAUUGUCAAAGGAGUUUUAUAGCAAACAGAAAAUCCGGCCCAGAAUUGGCUAAAACAUUUGGGGAGCUCACAUCAGGAAAUGAGAUUCGUUUUUAUUUCUUGAUUCUGCUGAAUUGGAUUGAAGGCAGCAGAAGGCAUUAAGUGGGAUUUGACCUGGAGGAAGGUGGCCUGGCGGUGCUCCUGGCUUCCCCGACCCUCCCUCCCUAGCCGUGUGUAGCAGGCACUCACUUUGCUUACAGCUUCCUCGGUGCCAUGUAUCUGUUUUUGGAAUCACACCUUGCCUGGAAGGCUGCUUGGACCCAUGGCCAGUGCCACACAGGGGCCUGGGCACCGGCUAACUGCAGACCCAGCCACCUGCUUCUUGACCACAGAAUUCGAGAUUUACUCAUGAGCUCUCUUGACGCACUGACUUUGGGAUGCAAACCAUUAUGACUAGGGGCACUUCCCGUGGCCUGGACUUCCACAAGGAAACCCUGGUUCCACCGUCAGGAAAGCUCCAAUACCUGGAAAGAGGUUGUACCUAAAGUGUUCUCUGUAUUGGCGGAAAAUGUUUCCCGGGCAACCUCUUUUCAUUGUGAAGGCUUGAAGAGCUUUUGGCUGACUUCCCAAAAGCAACCUGGGACACGCAAAUAGAAGCCAUCUGACGUCUGGUCUACCCAGUGCCAUGUAGAUUCGGGGAAUCUUCCUGGAGGUGACACCAACAUCGGCGAAGAUUCGGCAGUUCUGUUUUGAUUUUUUUUGUUUGUUUUUUGAUCAGUGCUAAUCUUCGAUACUCGAAGGAGAGGUUGUCCGUGUUGUCUUCUCUUUAUUUAUGAUGAAACAUACACGGGAAACCUCUUUUUUAGUAUCAAAUCCCACCCUGGAGGCACUUCCUGUUCCUGAUGCAGCCUUCAGGGAGGGACGUUGCCGGCUCCACUCUCGGUAGGCGCAAGCGAGGCUGACAGCGUGCCAUGCGUCGUGGGGGUGUGGCUCUCAGGCCCCAGCCAUGGAGGGCCCCUAGGAGGGGAAGCUGAGUUUGGAGAAGGGCCUGUGCUUCUGUGGUUGAAGGAGGUUGCUCAUUGUGGUGUUUGUCUAUUUGUUGAUUCACGGUGGGUGGCGCCUCUUCAGUGUGAGAUCUUGCUUGGAUGGCCUUCUGGACACGCUAGCAACGUCAUUGAAGGGACGAUGGUGCCAUCUGCUCUCCAGGGUAGCUGAGGGGAUGGUAGACCGGUGACGUGCACUUCAUUUACGAUGUAGGUCACCCGUUUGACUAUCCACCAGCGCCCGGUCCAUCUGUGGGAUGACAUCUUGGUGCACAUGGCAACUUCGGAGAAGAUGUGGGAGGACGUGGGGCCCGUGGGACUCUGCAGGAUUUUAGGAGGGGUUUCCCUUCGGGGCCCCCUCCUCCUACCUCGUUAAAAUCAAUAUAAGCAAUCAUCAGUGAAUAAUCUCUCUUUUGGUUUCAAAUCCUGCCCAGGAGGGCUGAUAGUCUGGCCACAGACAAUGCCAGGAUUGCAGAGGCCUGGGCUUCAGUGCCCCAUCAGGGAAAGUCCCACCCCACACCACAUGCUGACUGCAGGAGGUGUGUGUGUGACCUGGUACAGGGGUGUGGUUUAUCCUCGGAAGGGUUUGAGGAGUGUUGUGUGUGUGCAGGACAGGGCAGGCGUUGGGACAGCUGUGGUAGUGAGGGCCACUUUAUUCUGUGCUACAUGAAGAGAGGCUGUCUGACAAAGCUUGCCAUGUGUUUGAUGAAUGCUACGUGGCCCAUCUCUUUUCCAUAGGAGGACUUCCUGGACAUGAAGCUAGAUUCCGGCAGGGCCACUGGUGUCAGCAGCACUCCUGGUGAGUCGUGGAUGGGGGACUGAGGAGCUGGCAGCGUGAUUGAGAUGAGCCCUUCCUGUGUUGGGACCACUCAGAAUCCAGCCGCUUCGUGGGCAGCGUUCAGUCCAUGCUUGGGGAAAGGGCUUUGUUGCCGUUGCUCAUCUCUGUCUGUUGUUCAGCUCUGCUUGCCUUACGAGGCCCCAGAUGCCCUGGAUGCCCUCAGUGUCAGACUGCGGAAGAUGUGUCCCGGCUGUGACACGCGCUUCAGGGGAGGGCUGUUGGCGUCAGGUCCAUGGAGAGGUAUGGGAGUGGACAUCUUGUCUGAGAGCAGACAUUCUAUUUCGGGUGUGUGUCUUGGUCCGUUCAUCCUCAGUCUCCCUCCCAUACCUAGGAUGGCUUGUGGAGAGAAGGCCUGCCCUGAGGGCUGAAGUUGGGACCCACAGCUCUCACCCCGGCCUUGGUAUGCUCCCAUGGCUACGGCAGAGGCACAAGAAAGUAAUUAGAAACGCAGAAACUCCUUAAGGCCAAGGCUGGGAACUGCUAUAUUUCUACCCACAGAUCAUUGACCAGAACAAUUACACGGCCGAACCCAAGGCAAGGGGCGGGGAGGCCCACUCCACCCGGGAGGGGGUUGUGGUGAGGUGUGAAUGCAGGAACCGGUGAGGAUUUGCCACCACCAAGUCAGUUGUCCACGUGGACCACCUGAGAACUUGGGUUUUAUUCAUUGCUCAUUCAUCCCUCCCUAACCCGCAGCUUCCGGUCUGCCCCGGGGGCUCUUCUCCGGCUCAGGCUGAUCGACAGUGGUGACGCUGUGCCAGGACCCCUGGUCAUUCCAUCUGUUUGAGGCAAAUGUUAAAAAAUCCCUUGCGCUACCCAUUCUAUGACGACUCCCUUGGCUCAGAGGCUCCAUCAGGGCAGACACUUUGCUGUUUGUCCCUAAAGGGUGGGUGGUAGAUCUCAUCCAUCUUAUCUGGGGAGUUAUUGUGACUCUCCUGGUCCCUCCUCAUGUAUCCUCAGGAGGACUUUUAGGAUGCAAAAUCACUGUUUCUGUGCCAUUGUCAUAUUCUGUGCUACUGGAGGAGACUUUUUGUUAUUGAGAAAUUGAACACAUCGUGCUCACAAGCAGCUCCAGGACACAAUGCCACCUGUGCAGAGGGGGCAGACCUGUUAGAUGUCUCCCAGGUCUUGAGGGGGUUGUAUGCACGGCCAUAUCUUUGUCACCGGUUGCCCGGUGCGCAUCAGGACCCAUGUGCUCUCAGGAAGCCCGCAGGAGUGAUACCAGCCGCGGAGAAGCAGUGUUGUCAACGGUGCUGACGUGCGGUACUUAAUGAGAAGUUGCCCGUGUUUUUUUCGCUUUAUUUGUGACGAAACAUUCGCGGUGCACUUCUUUUUCAGUAUCCUAUUCUGCCUUGAAGACGUCUUGGUUUGGGUGCAACUUCAGGGAAGGCACAUGGGCCCCUGUAGUGGACGCUGAUCAGGACCUCCCUACCCCAUGUCUUUUCUCCUUCCUAAAUUUCUCCUUGUUUUUUUUUUUUUUUUUUUUUUUUAUGAAAGCUCCCGUCUUCCCGCCGUGUGCUUUGAUUGCAUUGACCCUGCCCCACUUCCUCCACCAGCCCAGGCUUAAGCGAAUCUCUUGAUCUCUUCUCCUUUGCCACUGCAAUUGCUUCCGGAAUAGGCCCAUGACCCCACUGGGCCAGUGAUAGGCAAGGAGAUGCUUGCUGCAGCUUCUGGGAAAGAAACUGUUUCUCCCUUUCCUGUGAUAGCUGCCAGAGUAGACACUGUCUAUUCCAUUCAGCUGGGAAUAGACAGUGAACUUUGACGUGAGCUUCGAAGGUCCCACAGCCGUUUAAGGACUGAGAGGAGAGGGCUUGGUGCCACGCAGACACAGCAGAGGGAGUCUGUACCAUGAAAGGCAUCUUGGAGACCUAGAGAAGAGCCUGGAUGAUAUCAUUUGAGUCCCUAGAUCAAACCCUGCCUGAAGCUUGCUCUGUCUCUGUACUUUUUAGUUAUAUACGUCUAUAAAUCCCUUACUUGUUUAAGCCAGUUGGAGUUAGAUCUUAUCUUACUUGCAAUACAAACAGAUGAUACCACAGUGUGUUUUCCAGUGUGACUGGGAAAGCCUGCAUUUUUUUCAAUGAUGUGUUUCUCACGGUUUGCCUAUCUAUCUUCAGUGUCCUAUUUAAGGCAGGGUUUUGGUGGAAGGUGACUUUUCUUAUGGACUUAUGCUUUCAAAGCUUUGUCUUAGUGAUUUAAUUUAUGGUUGACAAAUGAUGCACAAUUACCGUGUUUUGUGUCCAGCAAUGGGUCACUGGGUCCUCUCUGGAAGGCCUGAUGGAUGGUGGGCCCCAGAACUUCUGCCCCGAUUCACUCUCCCUCGAAUCCACCUCUCUCUGGGAGGCUGCCCUGCAAGUGAUGUGGACUUGGGGAAGCCGUUGUCCUUUCCUGGCCCCUGCUGUCCUUUGGCUCUCUGUGGGUUGGCUGUAUUUGUCACAACUCACACUUAACUGUCAGUGUUUUAGAACCAAGCCAUGCCUCCAGGGAACCCGGAGCACUUUAGAGAGGAGGUGCAGUGGUCAGCACCAUGCAAGGUGCACAGAGAGAUGGGUCCACCGAGAGCCGGGGCUGCCUUGGUGGUUUGUUUCUCCUGAUUCGAUAUCUUUGUCUUCCCAUCUCCUUCCUGGAACCAUGGGCUCAUGGAGGAGAUUCUAUUUUUGGGUCCAGGACCAUCCCAUUUUCUCUGAAGUGAUGCUCUCCAUGAGCAUUUGCAGGGUUGAUAGUAAACAUUCCGAAAGCCGUCUGCCCUGAUUAUUGAAUUCUGCCCAUGAAGACUUCCUGGGAUCCCGAAGUAGAGGGAGUCUGGGAUCGGUUUGCUUUAUCCGUGAUGACUGUCCGCCUCUGCUCAGUGUCAGCCCAGCCCUUCGAAGCAUGUCCCCCACCUCCCCUGGGGUGAGCCAACUUACCUGAUGCUUUUAGGCUUAAUUGAGCAUAAGUUUGAUUGGCAGCGUCUGCCCGGCCCUGCCCUCACGCCCUGACCCUCAGUGUCCCUUCACGCCCAGGUGUGCCUCUGGCAGGGAGGACGUGCUCAUCUCUGGUACCUGAAAAGAAGUUGCCCAUGUUAUUUUCGCUUUAUAUGUGACGAAACAAACAUGGUGCACUUCUUUUUCGGUAUCAAAUAUCUCCUUGAAGUGCCUCCAUCCCCGACGGGACCCUGAGCAUGGGACCUGGUGUCACUACCUCUCUUGGUAUGUACAUGGAGGAUUUGUCCUGGCAGCCCCUCGGUGACUUUGUGUGUUGGUGGGCUCAGGGACCAUGCUCAGUCCUCAGUCCUCAGUCCACGCCCACCUCUCGGACAGGCACAGUUGGCGAGGCCUCAACCACAUGCCAGUUCCCCGCUGCCAGGGAGGCUGGGGAGAUGCACUUCCAGGCUCCAUUGAGAAGCGUUCCCCAACAUUUGAGAAGAGUUCAGAUCAUAGCAGCCAAGAAAAAAAUAAAAAAGGAAGCAGCUGCCACAACAACAAAAACAAAUAAGCAAUGAAGACCCCUGCCCCCAUCCGCUCUCUCCAGAGGCUUGAGGGGAUGGCUGAAGGGGACAUGAGGACAUGCCAUCUGGGGGACUGCCACCCGCACCUCCACAGAAGAAUUGAUUGGGGGUAGCAAUUGUGGCAGAAGGCGUCCCUGUGGUUCUGGGAGAUGGGAUUUCUCAGAGUGGUGAUUUACUGGAGCCUAAUCCUCCCUGCCCCGCUCUUUCUUUACUUUUCUUUUCUUUUUUUCUUUCUUUUUUUUUUGACACAGAGUCUCGCACUGUCUCCUGGGCUGG